AGAGCACCAGGAGCUGGCUGGGGCUGGAGACUGGCGCUGCUGGAGCUGCAGCUGCCUGGCAGAGGGGAAACUGAGGUGGGGGUGUGGCUCUGGGACAGACAUCAGGGCAGGACCUCCCUAGCCAGGGUCCACGGUCUGGCUGGGGGAUGUGGACUGGCUGCAACGUGGGGCGGGGUUAAAGGUCUUCCAGGGCAGCCCUGGAGAGCACCACUCUGCAUUGAGCACCGCCCGGGCCACAGGCCUGCAGUGGCAGGAGCAUGAGUGAGCAGGGGAGGGAGACGGAGGAGGAGGAGGGGGGAGGUGGUGCUUCCGACACAGCGCCCAUGCUGCCCCGGGGACCUCCCGACCACCAGGCCUCAGCCCUGACGUGCCCAGGGUGGUCGGGGCCCCCGCUGCUGCCCGGCCGGCUGCUGGCCGGGCUCCUGCUGCACCUCCUGCUGCCCGCCGCAGCCUUCCUGCUGGUGCUCCUGCCCGCGGCCGCCGUCGUCUACCUGGGAUUCCUGUGCCACUCGAGGGUCCACCCCGCUCCGGGUCCCCGGUGCCGCGCGCUGUUCUCAGACCGCGGCUCCGCGGCGCUCAUCGUGUUCGGGCUUCUCUCGCUGCCGCCGCUGCUGGUGCUCGCCUCGGCCGUCCGCGCCCGCCUAGCCCGGCGCCUCCGCCCGCUGCUGCCUCCGCCCGCUGGGACCCCCGGACCCCGCCGCCCCCCGGGGCGCCCCGACGAGGACGAGCAACUCUGCGCCUGGGUGUGACCCGGCGGCCGCUGCGAAACCCCGGGAGGCCUCCGAGCUCGCGCGCGACCCCAUCGCGUGGCCCGGCCCGGAAAACUGAGGGUCGCCCCCGCUGCCCCUUCCUGGCUGGGCGCGCAGCGCUCCCGGCUUACGACCCCGGCCUCCCCCGCCCGCAGCCCCGCCCCCGCCACGGAGGGCAGGGGAGGGGAAGAGAGGGGAGGGGAGGGGAAGAGAGGGGAGGGGAGGGGGAGAGAGGGGAGGGGAGGGGAGGGGAAGAGGGGAGGGGAGGGGAAGAGAGGGGAGGGGAGGGGAAGAGAGGGGAGGGGAGGGGAAGAGAGGGGAGGGGAGGGGAAGAGGGGAGGGGAGGGGAGGGGAGGCAAAGAGAGGGGAGGUGAGGGAAAGAGAGGAGAGGGGAGGGGAAGAGAGGGGAGGGAAGGGCAGGGCAGGGCAGAGCCCGGCAGGCAGCCCUCAGAGGAGGGGCGCAGGCCCCAGCCCAAGGCCUCCCGCGCCUGCCCAGGUCCCGGCCUCCAUCGUCCAGGGCUCUGGGGCUCCCAGGGGAGACACCCACGCUCGGCCAAGCCCAGGGUUCCAGAAGCCCAGGGGUGGCGGCAGCCGGGCUCAGCCUAUGGCCAGGCUCGCAUUCAGACAUGCGCCAGCCUCGGUCGGCUCUCUCCGGGAGACACUAAGAUCUCCUCACUGACUUUGGUGUUCCUUGGUCUCACCAGCGCGUCCUAGCUGUGCCGAGCUCACACCCACCCUGUUUGGUGUAAGCCACAGGUCCACAACGUUCAUCAGCUCUGGAAAUCCCUCAACAAUUGUGUCCAGUUUCACCACGAAUUCCUUCUCCAUAUCCUCACCAUUUUCUUUUACCCCCUCAUCAAAUUACUCCCUUCCGUCUAAUCUGCUGAUUAACUCAUUCAUUUUAUCUUAAAUUAUUAUGUUAACAUAUCCAGGCCAGGCACGGUGGCUCACGCCUGUAAUCCCAGCACUUUGGGAAGCCGAGGAGGGCGGAUCACCAGCUCAGGAGAUCCAGAUCAUCCUGGCUAACACGGUGAAACCCCGUCUCUACUAAAAAAUACAGAAAUUAGCUGGGCUUGGUGGCGGGCACCUGUAGUACCAGCUACUCGGGAGGCUGAGGCAGGAGAAUGGCGUGAACCUGGGAGGCAAAGCUUGCAGUGAGCCAAGAUCACGCCACUGCACUCUAGCUUGGGCGAAAGAGCGAGGCUCCGUCUCAAAAAAAAAAAAAAAAAAAAUUAGCUGGGCGUGGUGGUGGGCACCUAUAACCUCAGCUACUUGGGAGGCUGAGGCAGGAGGAUCGCUUGAACCCAGGAGGCAGAGAUUGCAGUGAGCCGAAAUCAUGCCAUUGCACUCCAGCCUGGACAACAAGAGCAAGACUCCAUCUUAAAAACAAACAAAAAAACAACAAAAAAAAUUAGCUGGCCAUGGUGGUGCACACCUGUAGUCCCAGCUACUCAGGAGGCUGAGGCACAAGAAUCAUUUGAACACUGGAGGCAGAGGUUGGAGUGAGCUGAGAGGGUGCCACUGCACUCCAGCCUGGGUGACAAAGUGAAACUCCAUCUCAAAAAAAAAAAAAGGUUAGCAUAUCUAAAAGUUACAUCUGAUUGUGUUUUAGAUUUGUCUGAUUUUUUUUAUGGUCUCUUGAUACAUGCUUGCUUUUUAGAUUACAGUUUCCACUUCUUAAACAUAUUUCAUAUAUAGUUAUUUUAUAUUCUGUACUAAAUAAUUCCAGUGUCCUAGUCUUUGGGGGUCUAAAUCUGUGACUGGUGUUUCUGCCGAUUCUCAUCAGUAGCAUGGUGUUUCUCUGAACGUUUGGUUGUUUAAUUGUCAGCUGUUAUCGGAGACAAUUCUGAGGUCCAACUUGGGGAUGCUUCCCUCCAGAGACUAUUCCCCUUUUCCAGGCGAGACCACCCUCGGCCCCCUCAGUGACCCUUGAGACCCCUGGUUUAAGCAGCCCCUAGGCAGAGAAACAUACUUGUUCCCUGGCCGCAGGCUGGCUCUCUGUCCCUGUGUGUGUCCAGGGAGUUAUCUGCUUUCCCAACCACUUCCCUUCAUCAUCCAGGCCUCCACACUACUCUGUCUGUUUGUUUACUUAGAGACAGAGUCUUGCUCUGCCGCCCAGUCUGAGUGCAGUGGUGAGCUCCUAGCUCUCUGCAGCCUCGCCCUCCCAGGCUCAAGUGAUCCUCCUGCCUCAGCCUCCCAAGUAGCUGUGACUAGAGUGCACCACCACACCCAGCUAAUUUUAAAUUUUUUUGUAGAGACGGGGUCUCAUCAUGUUGCCCAGGCUGGUCUCGAACUCCUAGGCACAAGCAAUCCUCUCGCCUCAGCCUCCUAAAGUGUUGGGAUUACAGGCAUGAGCCACCCCACCUGGCCUUAUUUAUUUUUGCUGUUUAAUUUUGGGGGAGACUCGGAGAUAUUUACUUUCUUGGAAACACAACAGUCUAUUAAAAAUGUACGCUCAUAGUAAUUCA